CUUUACGCAGCUUGCUUUCCUGGCGCUGGGGGAGGGCGCAGCCGGGAAGUCCCAGAGCAGCGGUGUCAGGCUCUCCACCAAGGAGGGACUGGGCCAGAGUCCUCGCGAGGGCACGCGGCGUGGUCCCCAGAGCUAGGCCGGAGCGCGGGCCGCUGACGCCACUGUCGGGUGAGGCUCGGUGCAUCCAAGGGGAGCCGCCCUCCGUGCGGGGCGACCUCGUCUGCGCGGCGGGCGUGCCAGUUCCCCGCACCCAUGGCAGCGGCCAGAGAGCCGGAGUUGCCGCAGGAAGCCCCCGCCACGGAACCCGCGCCCCCGCCGGCCUGCCGCUUCUUCCUGGAAGGCCGCUGCCGCUUCGGCGCCCGCUGCCGCCAGCCCCACCCUGGGGCGCCGGCGCCGCCUGGCCGCGAGGCGCAGCCGGAGGCCGGGGCCAAGAAGCCGCCGCUGCGCACAGCCGCGGACGUCAUCCAGCGCAUCCGCUGGGACCCGCGCCUCGACCCCGCCGACUUCUCGGUGGGCUACGUCGACCGCUUUCUGGGUGUGCGCGAGGAGCCCUUCAGCGCCUUUUGCUGGGACCAGCCGCUGGCGGCGCUCGGGCCGGGCGUGCUGGCAGUGCCCCAGCACCGCGUGCGCUUCUUCCGCUUCCGUGGCCGCCUUGUGUGGGACCGCGCCUCGCGCACCGACCUCGUCUUUGGCUCUGGCUCGGCGGCGGGACGCGGGCCCACCAUCCUGGACGCACCGAACACCGAGGGCGCCCACGGGGCAGAGGGUGCCGAGUGGACACUGGCGGGGACAGGUCAGGAGGCCCAGGCUGCCCCCAAGCGAGGGAGCACAAGGCCGCUCUGCACAGGGCACCAGGAACCAGGCGUGGAGGAACCCGGAGAGCUGGAGGCGGCCCAGGAGAGGGCGCUGGGCACAGCUGCUGAUUUGGGAACACUGGCCCCAAGAGGACGCCUCGCCGGAGUGACUGAGGCACUGAAGCCAACAGCAGCCACCAGGACCACAUUGCUGGGGGGCAAGGAAGCACAGGCCCUGGGAGUCCCGGGGGGCUCCGCUGAGACGACAGAAGCCGAGUGGGGUCCUGCGGCCUGGCCCGAGGACAAAAGGGCCCGCCUUAGUGUUGCAGCCCCUUGCCAACCGCGCCCCACACAUUUUGUGGCCCUCAUGGUGACCGAGCCUGGGCUACAAGCAGAAGUGACCAAGGCCCAGGAAUACCUGGUCCACGUGGCCCCACACUGCGCCAACUUCCUAGUGCCCUCUCAGAACCUACACCUGACCCUGGCCCUGCUGCGACUGGCAGGCGCUGGGGAGGAGGCCGCUGCCAUUGGAGCUCUGAGACGGGCCCUCUUGGCCCCGGGGCUAAAUGCACCCCCUCGGCUGAGCUUUAGAAAGCUGGUCCUCCUGGGCCCGCAUGUGCUGUGUGCCCCACCCUCUCCCACACUGGAAAGCAUGGCACAAGUGCUGAGCCAGAGGCUGGAAGCCGAGGGGCUGAGUACACUACAGUCUCCAGGGCAGCUGCACCCCCACCUCACCGUGGCCAAGGUGCCCCAUGGUUCCCAGGUCCACCUCCCCAAGCUGGAGUUCACCCUCAGCCAGGAAGUGGGGUGCCAGCCCCUGCAGACACUCUGGCUGUGCCGUAUAGGGAGGACAGGGGGGCCUUUCCAGCCCCUGGCUGAGAUCCCCCUGGAGUGACACCCCCAGACCUCUGGAGGAGACAAUGGAUGCAAACAGCCCACACAGGAAAGACAAAGCAGGAGCGUGCACGCUCUCUCUUUCUCUCUUUAAUUUUGGUUUCUCUCAAGCUUCCAAAUGGUGCUCAGUGCUCCAAGGAAAGGAAGGAAGGAAGGAAAAGGAGGGGAGAGGAGGGGAAGGGGAGGCAGAGGAGGAACAUCUGGAAAAAAAGCAGCCUGACAGUCCAGCUGUUUGCAAACUCAUAGCACAUCCUCCAGUUACAUGGCAGAAGAGGGAGGGAGGGAGGGCCAAAAAGAAAAGGGAGAGGAGGAAGAAAAAUAACUUAAAUAAACACACACACAAAGAAAAGAGAAGGCAA